GAGGGCUGUGCGCGGUGGCGCGGGGGCGGAAAGCCGCAGGUCGGGCUCUCACCUGACCGUGGCUCGUUCCUAGAAGCGCAGUUUCCUAGUCGCUGCCUGUAGGGUCCACACUCGGACAGUAAAUUUGUGUUCAUCGCCGGGCGUGGUGGGGCCUGUGGUCCCAUCUACUCCGUAGGCUGAGGUGGAAGGAUCGCUUUAGCCCAGGAGGUGGAGGCUGCAGUGAGCCGAGAUCGCGCCACUGCACCCCUGUCUGGGCGACGGCGAGACCCCGUCUCCAAAAUGAUGAUAACGAUAACUACCAUUUUUGAGUACUAUGUGCUAGAUGCUUUUCAUGUGUUAUCUGAUUACUGUAGCCCUACCAGGUGCAGCCUGGCACCGUUUUAUUUCACUUAGAACUGAGAUUCCGAUAAAGUAACUUUUCCAAGGCAAGAGGUAGUCAGAGGCUGAGGAAUGAUUCAAAUUUAAGUCCAGCUCCAAAGCACCGGCCCAGUGUAGUCUGCAGAGUUCCAGCCCCAUAGAGCCACAUGGAGGAUGCGAGUGACAAUCGCCAAUCAACAAAUAGUUGAUGUAGAUUUCUUUAGUGAUGACUUAAUUGUUAGGGCCUGCUGGGAUUGUUCGAAAACCAGGGCUGAGAGUGGAAAGUGCAACUUCUGGGUGCAGGAGGAGCAAACAGGGCAACUGAUAGCAGUUUCCACAUUAGGAAGCUGCCCAGAGCUAAUUAUGACUGUCACAACACAGCCCCCCCUUAACUCAACACACCAAAAUAAAGAGCUUCGGUUCCGCUUUAGAUCCUGAAUUUGACUUCUUUGCAGGUUUAUACGAUGGUCUUAGUGUCAUGUGGGGUAAUUGUGAGGAUUUCGAUUGUAUUUAAUUCUCCAUGGAAAACCAGUACGGUUUGCUACUUUUUACAUGGCAGGGAAGGCUAAACUUUACCUCUGCCCAUCUUAGUUCGGAGUGACCCCUUUAACAAAUGAAAGGAUAACAAGAAAAAAGUUUAUUCUUGGACAGAGUACACAUCACAAGGGAUAAACCUUAAUGAGAAGUAACUUGAAAUGGUGGCUUAGAACUACAUUUGUAUACCAUCUUCAACAAAGAACUGUAGAUUUGCAGAGAAGUGACAGGACACAGGAGAGCAGUUUUAGGCUUCAAAGGGCAGGAAAUUGGGAAGGUAGAUACAUAUUCGGAAACUAAUGGAGUAAGAAUUGUUUGCAGAUUCCCCUGGUACCUUAACUGGUCUGGUAUUAAUAGGGGACCCUAUUACCACAUGUCUUUCUCCCUCAGUGUAUGAUAUAAUUUGUAAUCUUGGGUUUCAACUCAGAGAAAAUUGUGAUAUCAAUAGCAUUGUAACUCAGAAUGGUGAAGUAUGCUGGAAAACAAUCACAGACUGUGUGAGCUACACAGAGUCAGAGCAGGGUCUGGAUUACUGGGGAAGCGUGAGGCUGCUGGGCCCUGUGUGUGAGGCUGUCCAUUCACAUUUCUUAUCUCUGACCAAGGGGCAAUUUGAAAUUCGAUAUGCACCGUGGUUCCAGUGGACAAGUUUUCCAGAGUUAUUUCCUGAAAUAUUUGAUGCCUUGGAAAGUCUACAAUCUCCUGCUAUUUCUCUUAGCUUAAUGAAACUGACAUCGUGUCUAGAACGAGCCUUGGGUGAUGUAUUUUUACUGAUUGGGAAGGAAUGCCCCUUUCUUUUAAGAGAUCUGCUUUCAUCUGAGGAGCUUGCUCAAGUCUUCAGUCAGUCUGUGAUGAAUGUGCUAAAAGUCUUCGUUGGCUCUCCGUGUGGUCUCAACCUGCGUAACGUCUUAUGGCAUGGGUUUGCGUCACCUGAAGAAAUUCCUCCAAAAUACUGUUCAAUGAUGAUACUGUUGACGGCAGGAUUGGGUCAGUUACUGAAGAGUUACCUUCAAAACACUAAACUUACAUUGGCACAUCGCUCUUUCAUAUCUCUUACAAACCUCGAGGAUUUGAUUGUUUUUCCUGAUGUUACUUAUGAGGUGCUUUCAGUAUUAGAAGAAGUGAUGAUGAAAUCUGCUUUUAUAUUAAAAAUCAUGUUACCAUAUUGGGAAGUUGCACUGGUCAAGUUCAAGUCACACAGGUUUGCUGACUGCGCCAUAUUGUUGCUGACACAACUGGAGACUGGACUUAGGAAUGUUUUUGCCACACUUAACAGAUGUCCAAAAAGACUCCUGACUGCUGAGUCAACAGCUCUUUAUACCACCUUUGAUCAAAUAUUGGCAAAACACUUGAAUGAUGGUAAAAUCAAUCAGCUUCCUCUUUUCCUUGGAGAGCCUGCUAUGGAAUUUCUCUGGGAUUUCCUGAACCAUCAGGAGGGUCCCCGCAUAAGAGAUCAUUUAAGCCACGGGGAGAUCAACUUACAUGAAUUUUCAAAAGAAACAACUAAUCAGUUGCUUGCAUUUUCUCUUGUACUGCUACUCAGAUUCGUUGAUGACUGUCUGCUAUCAGUUUUUAAGGAAAAAUCAGCCGUAGAAUUGUUGAUUAGUCUUGCAGAAGGCUAUAGUUCUCGCUGUCAUCCGGUUUUUCAGCUUAAAAAACAGGUGCUGAGCUGUGAGGAGAGCAUCAGGGUUUGGGCUCUGCUGCCUUUCCCCGAAGAACUCACUCGGCAAGCCGUCAGAUUAGAAGAUAAUUCUGAAACAAAUGCCUGCCACUCUUUGAUUACAAAAAUGACGGAUGAGCUGUAUCACCAUAUGCCUGAGAAUCGUUGUGUGUUAAAGGACUUGGAUCGUCUUCCUACUGAGACGUGGCCCCAGCUUCUCCGUGAGCUCUGCAGCACACCUGUUCCCACCCUGUUCUGCCCCAGGAUUGUGCUGGAAGUGCUGGUUGUGCUCCGAAGCAUCAGCGAACAGUGCCGCCGUGUGUCCAGCCAGGUCACCGUUGCCUCAGAGCUGAGACACAGGCAGUGGGUGGAAAGGACGCUGCGGUCUCGCCAGCGGCAGAACUACCUGCGUAUGUGGAGUAGUAUCAGACUACUGUCCCCUGUGCUCAGCCUGAUACUGUUACUCAUUGCGCUGGAGUUGGUCAACAUUCAUGCUGUUUGUGGGAAGAAUGCGCAUGAGUAUCAGCAGUACCUAAAGUUUGUAAAGUCGAUCUUGCAGUACACGGAGAACCUGGUGGCUUACACCAGUUACGAAAAGAACAAGUGGAAUGAAACUAUCAAUCUUACACAUACAGCUUUGUUGAAAAUGUGGACUUUUAGUGAGAAGAAACAAAUGUUAAUACAUUUAGCCAAGAAAUCCACAAGUAAAGUACUCUUAUGAAAACUUGUAAGUCAGGAUGCUUUUAAUUUUAACAGAUUUUAACAGCGUGUAAAUUAAAAACCCAAAGACAGGGUGGAGUUGAGGGUC